AGACCUCAGAGUCCUUCAGAACUGGAGCCUCUGGGUUCUGCAGCCCUCCCACCCCAGGCCUGUGCUGGACACUGAGGGGACAAGCCAGCCCUGCAGGACUCCUCUGUGGACAUGAGUGCCCAAAUACAGGGUGGGGGCCUGAGAGGGGCAGAGGGAGGAGAGGCCUCUUCAGUGCCCAGAGAAGGUUCCCAGAAGGUUCUCGGGAAAGGCAGUGUCUGAGCUGCAUCUCACAGGAGGAGGGAGAGCACCUGCGCCCUCCUCCCGUCUCCACCAAGCUGCAGCCCCUCCCUCCUCUCCUCCCCCAAGACCUGGGCACAGAAGCUAGGCUCCUUCCGCCUCAUCUCCUUUAACAUGCCAAUUAGGCUCCCUCAGAGCCUGCAGUCCCACUUCCUGGUUCCACACUGCUGCCAUCCCCACAACUGAGGGGCGGCUCCAUGUCUGUGCCUCAGGCGCCUGAGCUGGUUCCUCGUGGGCCCUCCCCUGGGUGCCCUCUGAGCCCAGCUGCCCUCUGCCAUCCAGCAGGGGAGCCCAGCCUUCCUCUGAGGGCCCUCCCUGUGUCUUGCAGCCCCCAGAGCUGCCUCUGUCUCCCCCAAGCCCGCACUCCUCUCUGGCUGCCACACCAGGCCCAAGCCACACUGAGGUCACUUCGGCAUCAGCCCAGAGUUCACGGCCUUUGGGCACCUCAGGCCACAGGUCCCUCAUCCACCUUCCCUCAGGACAAACAUUAGCCCAGCCAUUGCCUAUUUACAUUAGAUAACUAGGUCAGCCUGGAGACAGGCACAGCUGGCAUUGCCAAGGGCUGUGGUUUCUAAUCUACAGAAGGGCUGGGCCACCCAGAGAAGGAGAUCAAAGAAUCAUAUCGUCAGAGACCUGGGGGAAGGACCUCAGAGGUUCUUGAUACUGCACAGGAGCGUUUCCCAAACUGUGCUCCCAGAAACACUUGCUCGGUAAUGUGCACUAUGAGAAAAGUGCUCCACGGUCAAGGAAGUGGGAAGACAGGCACCUUUUCCUGGCCUUGAUCGACCUUGCACAUGAACACAUACAUAGCCCUGAGAAAGCCUAGGCUCAAAUCAAAUGAUGGUGAAUCCUGUUAAAUUCAGCAUUUCCCCAAUUUAAUUGAGCCAAGCAACUCUUUUCUCAUCCAACAGUUGUUAACAUUCCAUGGAACUGGUAUUUCAGAAAAAUAACUUGAGUAAACACUGAUCAUAGAAUGUUGGCACUGAAAGGAACUUUAAAGAUCAUCAAAUCUUGGUGCUCCCCAAAAUAUUCAUAUUAAUAAUUCAUAUUUAUUGAUCUCAAUGUCCUAAGCAUGUUAAGUCUAUGAACUCAAUCAAGUCCCCACACCAAGUCUAUGAAGUGAGUACUUCAUUAUUCCCAUUUUACAGACGAGAAAACUGAGGCACAGUGGAUUAAGCAGUGUGGCCAAAGAUAAAGUUGUUUGGCUUCAGAGCCUGUGAUCUUCUCUACUCCACUAAACUGCAGAGAUCCUCUCCCUGUGUUCAGUAUUUCAAACAUACAACAAUAACUUAACUCCAUCUCAAAGAGUCAAUUAUCUCAGGCUAAUCAGACUUUCUGACUGGCAGAUGUGUGCUUAAUUAAUUUUGAUGGGGAAAGAAAUUAAUUAUGGUUCUAACAAUGAUUUAUUCAGUGCCUGCUCUAAAGAGUAUCCACACUGCACUGAUCACCACAUCGAACUUCAUAAAUAAAAUCUUCCAAAAUUUUGCCUCUGUGAAUGGGUGAGUGAACAGAGAAAAUAAUAAAAGGCAGUGGGAAAAGCUGGGAACCUCAUCUCUUGCCCUAUCUUCCAUGUCACAGAUGAGGAAACCUGAGGCCCAGAAGGAACUUGCCAAGACACAAAGCUGUCUUUGAUCAGGGUCAGGUCAGACCCCAGAUCUCCUGCCUCCUAGCCCCAUGCUCUUUCCUCUGCCCAAGGCUGUGGCCAGCAUCCUGGCCUUGUGGCCAGCUAGGCCAAGGGUAGGAGGUCAAGCAAGCAGACUAGCAGGCAUAGGAGGCCAGUGGGAAACAAGCAGCCAAGCCCAGUCCAGCCAAGGCCAUGACCAAGGGCUCAGAGUGGCUAGUUGUGCUUUGAAUAGAAGGAAAUAAGCCACAGGGAGAGAAAGACCAGUAAAAGGGAGGACCAGACCCAAUCCCACUCCCACACCACCAUCCCCACCCCGCAUCUCCCUGGAAGACAGCUUCAGCCAGUUUCUGACCUCCUUGGUGAUUCUGGGAGGAAAACAGAGGAACUGAGGUGGCCCAGGGUUUGCCUCUGAUCUCUUGGUUUUCCUGCUGCCCUAAAAUAUUUACACUAACAAUUAAUUUUUAUGUCCAGCCACCUGGCUUCCUUAGGUGGAUUCUGUGCCUCCAGCCAGGGUCCCAGGCCACCUCUUAGCUGAGUUGCUCCCAAGUAGGAGCUGCUGGGCCAUGAUUGAAUGAAGAGGCCCUGGUCAUACCUGAGCUGGAGGGCAGUGGACAGAGCAUUGGUUUUAGAACCAAGUAUCCUGGGUUAUAAUCCUGGUUCUGGCAUUCACAAGCUGUGUGACCUUGAACAGAUUGCUUUCCCUCUCUGGGCCUCCAUUUCCUCAUCUGUACGAUGUAAAGACUGAACCAAAUGAUGGCUAAGGGUAUUUCUGGAUCUGAGAACCUUAAAACCUAUGUUGGAUUCAGGGAGAGGAGGCUGGGAGAGGAGGCGGUAUGGAUAGUCCUGGUAGUUUUCUGAGAGGCAGUGGCCAGAGUCUCCCGGUCAGAACAUCUGCUCUGGUUGAUCAGCCCAGCAGGUACUGCGAGAGAGGGUCCUCAGAGAGUCAGCCACACAGAAGGACAGAUGCAGCCCCUCACCCAGAGACUCGAAGGCCUGGACAGAGGAGAGAAGAUAGAGAACACCUUUUGCCCCCUGCCUCAUAAAGCCAAGCGCGACAUGGGCAAGGACCAGGCAGGCAGCGGGCCUGCUGGCAGGCAGACGGGUCUUGCCAAACUCCCACUUACUUCCCAGAAGCUCCAGGGCCCCCUGGGAGUGGCUCCACCCAGCUGGCACCCCUCCAAGUUGGGCGCCCACGUCAGCAGGUCCUCACACUCCCUUGCCCUUUCACCCAGUGACAAUGGGACAGGCAAUGGGGUGGGGGGCACCCUAAGCCGGAUACUUGGAGAAGCGUCUGACUGCCUGAGCAUGGCCCUCCUGUUACCACCUCUGCUGCAACUGGCUCAGAGCAACGCCUGAGGCUGAUGCCCAAGUGAAAUGCUCUCCUCCCAAGGCCUCCCGGCCUGGUCGCCCUUCCUGGGUGAUGCAUUGGCUCCCACGUACCGGAAUGAAUGCUGAGUCAGAAAGGCCCAGUGGCCUUGGCCAACACCCAAGGCCUCUCUGGACUUCAUGACACCAACUGUAAUAUGAAGAUAAUCAUAAUAGUGACCUUGUAAGAAGUUUUUGAGGAUUAAGUUAAAAAUACAUCUGAAGGGCUACGGGCACGCGGCACCCAGCACGGAUGGCGGCAAGGUGUUCUGCAUGUUCUACGCGCUGCUGGGCAUCCCGCUCACGCUCGUCAUGUUCCAGAGCCUGGGCGAGCGCAUCAACACCUUGGUGAGGUACCUGCUGCACCGCGCCAAGAAGGGGCUGGGCAUGCGGCGCGCCGACGUGUCCAUGGCCAACAUGGUGCUCAUCGGCUUCUUCUCGUGCAUCAGCACGCUGUGCAUCGGCGCCGCCGCCUUCUCCCACUACGAGCACUGGACCUUCUUCCAGGCCUACUACUACUGCUUCAUCACCCUCACCACCAUCGGCUUCGGCGACUACGUGGCGCUGCAGAAGGACCAGGCCCUGCAGACGCAGCCGCAGUACGUGGCCUUCAGCUUCGUCUACAUCCUUACGGGCCUCACGGUCAUCGGCGCCUUCCUCAACCUCGUGGUGCUGCGCUUCAUGACCAUGAACGCCGAGGACGAGAAGCGCGACGCCGAGCACCGCGCGCUGCUCACGCGCAACGGGCAGGCGGGCGGCGGCGGAGGGGGUGGCAGCGCGCACACUACGGACACCGCCUCAUCCACGGCGGCAGCGGGCGGCGGCGGCUUCCGCAACGUCUACGCGGAGGUGCUGCACUUCCAGUCCAUGUGCUCGUGCCUGUGGUACAAGAGCCGCGAGAAGCUGCAGUACUCCAUCCCCAUGAUCAUCCCGCGGGACCUCUCCACGUCCGACACGUGCGUGGAGCAGAGCCACUCGUCGCCGGGAGGGGGCGGCCGCUACAGCGACACGCCCUCGCGACGCUGCCUGUGCAGCGGGGCGCCACGCUCCGCCAUCAGCUCGGUGUCCACGGGUCUGCACAGCCUGUCCACCUUCCGCGGCCUCAUGAAGCGCAGGAGCUCCGUGUGACUGCCCCGAGGGGCCUGGAGCACCUGGGGGCGCGGGCGGGGGACCCCUGCUGGGAGGCCAGGAGACUGCCCCUGCUGCCUUCUGCCCAGUGGGACCCCGCACAACAUCCCUCACCACUCUCCCCCAGCACCCCCAUCUCCGACUGUGCCUGCUUGCACCAGCCGGCAGGAGGCCGGGCUCUGAGGACCCCUGGGGCCCCCAUCGGAGCCCUGCAAAUUCCGAGAAAUGUGAAACUUGGUGGGGUCAGGGAGGAAAGGCAGAAGCUGGGAGCCUCCCUUCCCUUUGAAAAUCUAAGAAGCUCCCAGUCCUCAGAGACCCUGCUGGUACCCAGACCCCCACCUUCGGAGGGGACUUCAUGUUCCGUGUACGUUUGCAUCUCUAUUUAUACCUCUGUCCUGCUAGGUCUCCCACCUUCCCUUGGUUCCAAAAGCCAGGGUGUCUAUGUCCAAGUCACCCCUACUCAGCCCCACUCCCCUUCCUCAUCCCCAGCUGUGUCUCCCAACCUCCCUUCGUGUUGUUUUGCAUGGCUUUGCAGUUAUGGAGAAAGUGGAAACCCAGCAGUCCCUAAAGCUGGUCCCCAGAAAGCAGGACAGAAAGAAGGAGGGACAGGCAGGCAGCAGGAGGGGCGAGCUGGGAGGCAGGAGGCAGCGGCCUGUCAGUCUGCAGAAUGGUCGCACUGGAGGUUCAAGCUAACUGGCCUCCAGCCACAUUCUCAUAGCAGGUAGGACUUCAGCCUUCCAGACACUGCCCUUAGAAUCUGGAACAGAAGACUUCAGACUCACCAUAAUUGCUGAUAAUUACCCACUCUUAAAUUUGUCGAGUGAUUUUUAGCCUCUGAAAACUCUAUGCUGGCCACUGAUUCCUUUGAGUCUCACAAAACCCUACUUAGGUCAUCAGGGCAGGAGUUCUCACUCCCAUUUUACAGAUGAGAAUACUGAGGCCUGGACAGGUGAAGUGACCAGAGAGCAAAAGGCAAAGGGGUGGGGGCUGGGUGCAGUGGCUCACACCUGUAUUCCCAACACUUUUGGAGGCUGAGGUUGGAGGAUUGCUUGAGCCCAGGAAUUUGAGACCAGCCUAGGUGACAUAGUGAGACCCCAUCUCUACAAAAAAUAAAAAAUUAACCAGGUGUGGUGGCACGUGCCUGGGAGUCCCAGCGACUUGGGAGGCUGAGGUGGGAGGAUUGUUUGAGCCUGGGAGGUCGAGGCUGUAGUGAGCCCUGAUUGCACCACUGUACUCCAGCCUGGGUGACAGGGCAAGACCCUGUCUCAAAAAAAAAAAAAAAAAUGGCAAAGGGAGACAAGAGCCCAGCCUGCUUGUUGCUAGCCAAAGUGUUCUUUCCUUCCAGCUUGGCCUGCUCUUAAAAGCAAAGCUCCUGCAGUGUACAUCCUGGCAUUGUGUGGCUACCUGGGUUUUAAACCAGAAUCAGAAGUCCCGGAUCAGAGGGCACUGCUGAGGUUCAGCCUCUUCUCUUCUUGGCCAGGAGGCAGCAGCUCUGAAUGGGCCCCUGAGGCUGCACAGGGGCCUUUGUCACUGGGGCGCAUGCUUACAAACAGUGCAGUUCUUGGGACCGAGGUAAGCAGGGCUGGGUCUCAUGGCAGAAAGGCCAGGAUCUGGGGCUCUAGGAAUUUGGGAAUUGGGCAGAGUGGCCAAGAAAGCUGGCAGGCAUAUCCUAUGGGACAUCACACCUGGCACCAUUGUCAUUGUUGGUGCCUGUGUCCCAAGUAGCUAGUGAUAAGCUGAGGCUGCAGCAAGAAACACCCUUCCCAGGUGGGGGAGUUUGGACCAGAGGUGCCCUCUGCCCACCACACCUGCAACCCAGAAGCCCAGAUGGAACGCAGCUGACGAAGGUGAUGCUUGAGGCUCACUUUUGGGGCCCCACAGCUGGAGCCGGUAUAAUGACUGGGACAACAUCAAGGGGUGGAUGAGGGGCCUCUCCUCCCGCAACACUGCCUUCCCAUGCUGUUCCCCUGCCAGCUCCUUAACACUGCCGACCAAGGCCAGCCCUGGCAUUCAGGGAAAUUGGAGGGCAGCACCCGUAGGGUGGCCAGCCUCAGGCCCCACCCCAGCUGUGUCCUCUAGUCUCUGGGGACCCCUGGGGGGAAGAAGUCUACCCUGCUUGUGAGUCCCGUCUCAGUGUGGAGGAACUGGCUGCACGUGGGACCUGAAGGUGCCCUCUGUGUUUAUGUUGGGGGUGGGGGGGCAGUGCUGGCUGCCUCUGUCCUGUGUGUGACCCUGCCCUCGAAGGGUCCUGUCCUGUCAGUCCCGAGGGAGCCACAACCAAAGCUGCGGAGAGAAGGUGGGGAAGGGUGCAGAAUGGCCGUGGGGCACAGCGUGGCAGACUGUUCAGUCUCUGCUGGGUCUUUCCUAGGGACCUGGAAGGCCAGUGUUGCUUCCCCCUCACUCCCUUUCACUGCAGGCAGCCUCUCUGCUUCCCCAAUGCCUUAUGCCUGGGCACACUGCCACAGAAUAUGCAAUAUGUGUGGGUGACCAUGCCCUCACGACCACACCCCCACCCCGGGCAGCCCCCGGACUCCAAAGGUCGUGGCUGCCACAGCCUCCCUCAGCUCUUCCUGCCUAUCUGUCUUCACACUGAGAAUGGCGCCCAAUAAAUGCUAUCCACGGAGACCAGGCUCAGGCUCCAGCUGCCUCUGUCAUCGUAUGCCCUUGCUGCUGCCAGGGAGGGGCCAUCUCCCACCCCCUCCCCUGCCGGGGUCUACAAACAUAUCUAGCUGCUGGGUGCCGUGGCUCACACCUAUAGUCACAGCACUAGGCGGGCAGAUCACCUGAGGUCAGAAGUUCAAGACCAGCCUGGCCAACAUGGUAAAACCCCGUCUCUACUAAAAAUACAAAAAUUAGCUGAGCGUGGUGGCGCAUGUCUGUAGUCCCAGCUACUCGGCUACUCAGGAGGCUGACGCACGAGAAUCGCUUGAACCCGGGAGGCGGAGGUUGCAGUGAGCUGAGAUCGUGCCACUGCACUCCAGCCUGAGCGACAGAGUGAGACCCUGUCUAAAAAAAAACAAUAAUAAUAAAAUAAAAUAACAUACCUAGCUGACUCGCCAUGGGCUCGCUGGCCUGUGGGCGACACUGGCUUCCCUUUUGGGAUUUCCCAGAAGAUCCAGAUUUUCUUAAGUCCCCUUGGAACAGACUAAGAAAGGAUCACCUUAGAAAUCACCUGGUCCUAUUGUCCCCCCCGUACAUGAGUAACUGAGGCCCACAGAGAGCAAAUCGCCUGCCUGAGUCACACAGCAGUGAGUGGCAGACCUAGGCUAGGAACUAGGACUGGGGAUUGCUAUUCCAGUGCUCCCCAUCCUCACACAGACUGCACAGUCCGCCUGGACACACCCCAGCUGACAGUGGUACCUCCCAGUCAGCCAGGAGAAUGGAUUCCUUCUCCUGCAGUAGGGGCCCCCUGGCUGAGUGGCCUGAUUGACUAAAACAUAUGUCUUUGAAGGAGAGUGCAUCACAAGCACCUUUCUUUGGGGUAGAUUUUUCUCUGGGUCUAGAGGGACAGCUCAGGCUUGGGACUGGGCCUCAGAACCUACGACAGACCGUGAGAGCAGACCCACCUUAUCCAUCUGGUGCCAGCUCCCCAGGUCAGCUACAGCGACCCCCGGACUUCAUAGAGUACAAUCCACAGUAAUAGCACACAGCUCUGUACCUAUCUAGCUCCAUGCCUAUCUAUCUGCCUACCUUUCACAAAAUAAUUCUUAGCAACCCUGCUACAGCCAAUGAUUCUAAUACGUUCUGUUCUAUUGCAUGUUAUAAAAUGCUGGUCACGAUCCACUAAAUUGAUGUCUCUACCUGCUAAUGGUUUAAUACCUGCAGAUUGAAAUAUACUGGAGAAAUAAAGAGAGUGGGAGUAGGGACACUUUCUCCCAGUGCCCACACCGCCCCUCGUUACCCGCAUAGGUCAACUGAAAGAUACAGAGAGGGAAGCUUUGAUGGGGGGUUCAGAGUUCAAAGGAAGAAAUGAUGGCACCUGCACUCCCUGCCCCCAGAGGCAGGACACAGCCAGCCCUCCUGUGACAGCACUCCUGGCAGCUCCUUGUUGGCCUGCAGCCCUCAGGGGGCUUAGUUGCCAUUGACUCACCCACUCCUAAGGCCACCACAUCAAAAUCUGAGGCUUACUGCCCUGUCCCACCUGCCUCUGUCUUUCUUAAAACAGCUAAAUGCAACAAUAGCAGAAAUUAGCUUGUUUUUGAGGUUGGCAAUGACCAGUUCAAGGUGACUCUUAUUUUCUUAAGCAGUGCUUGCAGGACAUAAAUGUGAUGACACUUGCCCUCCUUUCUUUAUCGCCUGGGACAGACUUUACAAACAGACCUGGGAGAAGUCCCCUAAGGGGCUGCAUUUAUCCCCAUCUCCCUAGGGGUGAUCAGCAUUGUGACAGCUGGGCAGAGCAGUGGUGAACUGCACCCAUGUCCCUGCUCACAUCUCCUAAGAUCUCAGAAUUGCCUGAGGUUCUAGCGUGGGCUCCUUCUCUCCAGAUGAUGCCAUCCCCACCCCCCUCAUUUCCACACAGCAUCUGAGGCAUCCUGCACUAAAAGAUAUAUGUACAGCAAAACAAAAAUAGAAAACCAGCACAGCAGAGUGGAGGUGGGGUAUAAAUAUACCCAGAUCCCCGCUGAUUUGGUUACUCGGGGUGAGCAUCAGAUGGAAAUAGAAGUUUCCGGGGGCCAAGAGAGAAAGAGGGAUGUAACGACAAUUCUUUUCAAAACGUGUCCCAUGGUAUGCCUCGUGGAAAAAAUGGUUCGUUGGUCAAAUGAAUUUGGGAAAAUGCUGUCAAUAUCACCGACUCAUGGAGCUUCGCAAGGCAUCUUAGCUUAAUAAAGGUUAUGAAAAGUCUUGCAGCAAA